CGUCGGGUUUCCUCGUUUUUGCGGACUGGCGCUUUCUGAUUUCAGAGACUCUCCGCAACAGAACCAUCUCAAGUGGGUCUACCUCCUCGCCUUUUUUUGUUGUUGUUGUUGCUUGGCUGCGCUUCUGACAGGGCAGGCCGUGAUGAUGUUUGUUUAUGAGUUAGGUCUGACUGUUCGUUGGUGCUUAAGAUCCCCACCGGGUCCCUAGGGCCUGUGCGUACCGCGCACCUGUGCACGUCCUGCGCGCAGCUGCAGGCGACUCCGCUCUGGCUCGUCGCUGCUGUUUCCUGCUGGGGGUGCCGACCCUGUCCCACGCUAGCUGGGUGACUUCCCCCAACCGCAGAGACAGCGGCGACCCGGGGCCUCAGACCUGCCCCCGCAUCUCGCCGGCGCCAGGCAGUGGGAAGUCAGGUUCUUCCGCCACCUCCCAGCCAGGACUCUGCCACCCUCCCUCAGGAUGCCUGAGGGCCCCGAGCUGCACCUGGCCAGCCAGUUUGUGAAUGAGGCCUGCAGGGCGCUGGUGUUCGGCGGCUGCGUGGAGAAGUCCUCUGUCAGCCGCAACCCUGAGGUGCCCUUUGAGAGCAGUGCCUACCGCAUCUCAGCUUCAGCCCGCGGCAAGGAGCUGCGCCUGAUACUGAGCCCUCUGCCUGGGGCCCAGCCCCAACAGGAGCCACUGGCCCUGGUCUUCCGCUUCGGCAUGUCCGGCUCUUUUCAGCUGGUGCCCCGCGAGGAGCUGCCACGCCAUGCCCACCUGCGCUUUUACACGGCCCCGCCUGGCCCCCGGCUCGCCCUAUGUUUCGUGGACAUCCGCCGGUUCGGCCGCUGGGACCUUGGGGGAAAGUGGCAGCCGGGCCGCGGGCCCUGUGUCUUGCAGGAGUACCAGCAGUUCAGGGAGAAUGUGCUACGAAACCUAGCGGAUAAGGCCUUUGACCGGCCCAUCUGCGAGGCCCUCCUGGACCAGAGGUUCUUCAAUGGCAUUGGCAACUAUCUGCGGGCAGAGAUCCUGUACCGGCUGAAGAUCCCCCCCUUUGAGAAGGCCCGCUCGGUCCUGGAGGCCCUGCAGCAGCACAGGCCGAGCCCGGAGCUGACCCUGAGCCAGAAGAUAAGGACCAAGCUGCAGAAUCCAGACCUGCUGGAGCUAUGUCACUCAGUGCCCAAGGAAGUGGUCCAGUUGGGGGGCAAAGGCUACGGGUCAGAGAGCGGGGAGGAGGACUUUGCUGCCUUUCGAGCCUGGCUGCGCUGCUAUGGCAUGCCAGGCAUGAGCUCCCUGCAGGACCGGCAUGGCCGUACCAUCUGGUUCCAGGGGGAUCCUGGACCGUUGGCACCCAAAGGGCGCAAGUCCCGCAAAAAGAAAUCCAAGGCCACACAGCUGAGUCCUGAGGACAGAGUGGAGGACGCUUUGCCUCCAAGCAAGGCCCCUUCCAGGACACGAAGGGCAAAGAGAGACCUUCCUAAGAGGACUGCAACCCAGCGGCCUGAGGGGACCAGCCUCCAGCAGGACCCAGAAGCUCCCACAGUGCCCAAGAAGGGGAGGAGGAAGGGGCGACAGGCAGCCUCUGGCCACUGCAGACCCCGGAAGGUCAAGGCUGACAUCCCAUCCUUGGAACCAGAGGGGACCUCAGCCUCUUAGCAGGAGGCUCUCCUUGCUUGCACUCACCCUUUCUUAUUGUCUUGCCCUGCAUCUGGGGGUCUGAAUUUUUGGGAGCAGGCAAUAUCUGAAGGUGCAAACAGGCCCUACGGCUGUUCCCUGCACAACUCUCAUGGUUUUAAUUGUACCCCAUCUUCCACAUCUUUAAAGCUCAUGUGAAAAAUGCUGCAUUUUUAAUAAACUGAUACAUUUGAACUUCUUGGCACCUCUUGGUCUGAGAUGGCCAGGUAGGAAGGGCCUGCUGUCCGGUCCUGGUGACAGAAGGCCCAGCUCCUCACAAGGCAAACUGAGCCCCCAUCCCAGUCCUCAAGGCUCUGACUCUAUCAGAGGACAGUUUGCCUCUGCAAGGACAGCCCCUCAGAGGUGGUACAAAGACCCUGGCCCCAGGCAGCCCAGGAGCCAGAGCUCCUCCAGUCCAGAUUCUCCAGGGUCCAGGGCUGCCCCCUCAUCCUGGCAGGAGCCAGGCAAAACCCACCCUUCGGCCCCUCCCCAGCCCCAGGCCCAGGCCCUUUACCUGCUGGCACAGGGGAGGGGCUUCUCAACUCAUGGUCUCUUCACUGGCUUUUGGUGGCUCGAGGUCCCCAGUCUCUCCUGUGGGGGCUGCAACCCAGACCCUGCACGCACAGGUACCUUAGGAUCUUGCCCCUACCCACCAAAUACCUGGGAAGCCAUCCCACCCCAGACUUCCCACCCCCACCCCAAGCGUGAGGAUGGGCCCUAAGGGGACUGAGCAGCAGGGUUCCCGAUCCAAGGAUUUAUUCCACAAGAAAAGACUGAUCCCUGCUUUAGGCUGGGGAAGCAGAAAUUAGGAGUCCCCAGAGCCUUCUACAAACAAAACCCCAGCCCCAGGGACUCAGUGUGGCGGAGGCUGAAGCACGAGCAACAGGGACAGCACUUGGAAGGGAGAAAAGGUGAGCUUCAGGCGGUUGUCCCGAAGGGUCAAGUGGCCAGCAGGGUCUGGUCGCUCCAAGAGAUCGCAGCUGGAGAACAGGAGGGGCCAUGAAGGCUCUGCGAGGGCGAGACUCGACCCCCGCCCCAAUCCCACACCGCCACUCACAGGAUGGCCUCCUGAACCGGCAGCGACAAGUGCAGCCAGCAGUCCACGUGGCUGCCGUGGGCCUCAUACAGCCUCAGGACCAGCGAGCGGCGCUGGGGGCUGCUCUCCGCCUGCAGAGGAACACGUCUGGUGGGAGGGGCCGAGGGCAGGCCCAGUUCGGAACCCCGUCCCCAGCACGUCCCACCCCUUGCCUGCUUGACGGUCUCCAAUACGACCGCGGGUGAAGACACGGAAAACGCACUCCAGGAGGUGGCGGGCGCUGGGCUGGGGGCUGGCAGAGCCAACAGGGGGAAGUUUAGGCUGUAGGCAGCUUGGAUAACGCCAGCAUCCUGGAAAGAGCCUGGGGUACGACCAGGAAACAAUGCUGGUGGAGAAUGGGGGCUACCCUCCCCUGUCCCUAGAAGGGGCAGGAAGCCAGGUUGCUGGGGUUUGGGCUCAGGGAAGGGCAGAGAGGUGUCUAGGGCUGCAGGAAGGCCCCACCGUCCCCAGCACUCACCCUUGUGCGGCAUCAGUGCAUAGGUGAACUCGUGGCGCCCCGUGUCAGCAGUAGCGUCCGGGGCUUUAGGCGCCCGCAAGCUGGGGUGAGGAGGGCGCGUAGGGGCCACGCUGAAGCUGUUGGAGUUGUGGUCGGGAAGACCCAUUUCUCCAUGCCAGCUCCCAGGCCUGGUGGGUACCCCACUUACAGCGAGAGGCUGAGGAUGCUGCCUCGCACUGACGCGCCAUACUUGCAGUCGUUGAGCAGGGCCAGCCCAAAGCCGUGUUCUGACAGAUCCAUCCAGCGAUGGGCCCACACCUGGAGGGCAGAUCCAAGACCCACUUGGUGGCCCUGUGCCCCUCUUUGUGCUCCCAGACUCCAGAGCUCCUGUCACUAGGCCGAGCACAAGCUCUAGAACCACACAACUGAACUCCAGCUCCCACUGUACGGGGCCCUGGGCAUGCCACCCAACCUGCCUAAGCCUCAGUUUCCUUAUCUGUGAAACGGGAAUAAAUAAUAGUACUCACCCCA